GGAGUUACCUCGCGGACGGCGGAAGGUGGACUCGCGAAUGUUAGGCCUGUGGGUGCCAUAGCGACCGGGAGGUUGGGCUGGCCAGAUUCAGCUGCCGGGACCGGACCAGGUGCUUAGGAGAACAUGCAGUAGAACUUUUCAUCAAACAAAUGGAACACGUCACAGAAUUUUGCUAACAUGGACAACUCUGCACAGAAAAAUGAACGCACUGGCAAACAUCCCAGACGUGCCAGUGAAGUACAGAAAGGCCAAGGAGCAGUGAGGACGCUUCCUCUGUCCUGACCGCGCCUCGUCCAGGCUGCUCCCAGAAUAGUUUUGCUGUCUCCUUCCUGCCUGGCAAGAAUGUCUUUACUAUCAUCUCCUUCCUUUUCUCCGGGACAGCCUGUUUAAGGUUUUACUGCUGCAUAUCCAACACAAUCCUCCAUUCCUUUUAAAUCUCAAGCUUCAGUAAUCCCAGAAUCAGAAAAAAAAGGAUUCAAUAGUCAAGCCAAGAGAUUUCCUCAUAAGAAGAAUGAUAUCCCAGGACCUGGGUUCUACAAUGUUAUUCACCAGUCACCGGUGUCCAACAGUGUCUCAUUGUCCAAGAAAGGAACUUGCAUGUUUCCCUCAAUGUGCGCCCGAUUGGACACCAUCAUUUCUAAAUACCCUGCAGCGAAUGCAUACACUAUCCCAUCGGAUUUUAUUUCCAAGAGAGACUUUAGUAAUUCGUGUUCCAGCAUGUUCCAGUUGCCAAGCUUUAUGAAAGCUCUCAAGUUUGAAACUCCUGCACCAAACUAUUACAAUGCCUCUGUCUCUUGCUGCAAGCAGAGAAACAACGUCUGUACUCGAGCCGGGUUUAUGUCAAAAACCCAAAGAGGAUCUUUCGCUUUUGCUGAUAAAGGACCUCCCCCAGGGCAUUAUGAUAUCAACGAAUCCCUUGUGAAGCAGUCGCCAAAUACAUUAAUGUCUUGUUUUAAAUCAAAAACCAACCGUGGAUUAAAACUGACGUCAACAGGCCCGGGACCUGGUUAUUACAACCCCAGUGAUUGCACAAAAGUUCCAAAAAAGACUCUUUUCCCGAAAAACCCCAUCCUGAACUUCUCUGCUCAGCCUUCGCCUCUGCCUCCGAAGCCACCUUUCCCAGGUCCUGGUCAGUAUGAGAUCGUGGACUACUUAGGCCCCCGCAAGCAUUUCAUCUCUAGUGCAUCAUUCGUGUCCAAUACCAGCCGGUGGACAGCGGCGCCGCCUCAGCCAGGCCUGCCUGGCCCAGCUACGUACAAGCCAGAGCUUCCAGGAAAGCAGUCCUUCCUCUACAACGAGGACAAGAAAUGGAUCCCGGUUCUGUAGGGAUGUCACACAAGGUCAAGGAGAACUCCAGCCACCAGCCCACCCUGCCCAGCGUCCCCAGGACAUUCCUCAGGAGGAGACCGAUCAUGAGUGUGGCAGCUGACAACUUGGGGGGUGGCUCUACCACUCUGGCCUGGCAUCCUAGCCGGACUGCUGCCAUUGCCUUUGUCUUGAGCUGGAGACAUUGCUCCCUGGAGACUUCACCCCAGCCCCACAGACUCCAGUGGCUUCCUGAGCAGAAGGGAGGAGUGGACAGAGCCCCCUGGCUGCUUCCCCACGCACCCAUCCAGGCUGCCUUCCGGCACGACUCCCUGCCGCAGACUGAAGGGACUCCUGAAGCGCAGACUUCAAGGAGGAUCAGUCCACCCUGAAGGUGGCCAAGCCUGGAAGCCCCACCCUUCCCUGUUUCAUUCCUUCAUUCAUUUACACAUUCAUUCAUUCCCUCACUCCUGCCUUUCUCAUUUGUCCCUUUCUGACCUCACUCACUUACGGUAUGUCUACUGGGCGAAAGCUACCUGCAGGCAGGUGAUGCUUUUUCCACCAGUCCACAGCUUCCUUUCUAAAGUGACCACCUGUUUGGAAAGACCUCUCUUUACUCCUUUUAGACCUUUUUCUCUUUGGAGUGGGAGAUCAUCUUGGAAUGGCAGUGGCCGGGCCCGGGGGCUGCGCUUUUCCCUGACUUUCUCUGCUGGCGGGACUGAAUUUUCUCAAGGCUUACAGGCCCUUCCAUGGAGUCCACAUGGCCUGUCUAGGCCUGAUAGCUUUCGUCUCUCUAUGUGGAGGGAAAAAGAAAUGUGCCCUAGUGGUUUUGGUGGAGGCUGCACAGAUUCGCGGUGGGUGGGGAGCUGCCAGGCUCCUUUUCUGAUCUCCCAGCAGGCUUUGACUGACGCUGUUUAGUCUUUCUGUACAUUAACCCCGCCAGAUACCGAGAGGUUACAAAGCCUCCAAGGCCUGUACAACUGUGGCCUCUCCAGAGAAGUGGUUCUCAGCCUUGACUGCACACUGUAAUCACCUGGGGACUUUAAAAAGUACUGAGGCCUGGGGCCCACCCACAAAUGCUGAUUUAACUCCUCCAGGGUGGGGUCUGGGCAGUGGGGAGGCAGGAGCCACCCAGGUGAUUCCAAUGAUAGGUGUAGGUUGAGAAGCGCCACCUUCCAGCUUCCUAACUGGCUCUGGGAGGGGAGCUGGGUGGGAAGUUCAGGAGGUGGGAACUUUGUACACGCAGAGCACCUGGAGCACCUACAGCAUGGCUGUGGUUCCACACUCCUCUGUCAUUUAACCUUCACACAUCACCUCGUUCUGACAUCAAGGGUGCGUCACAGCCACAGUGAGGCCUCGCCUGGGCAGAGCAACUCUGGGUGCCCCACUGGGUCCCUCCCACAGGGGCAGGCAAGCCUAAUGGGAACCCGAGGCAAAAGGAAACAUCAGUAAUACGAAUCCUGUCUUUAAAACUGUGAUGUUUUGUUCACCAUGGAUUUUUUUUUUGGGGGGGGGGGCCUUAAUUUUAAAAAUAUUGCAUUAAACUUAUUUAUCUUGCUUAUUGA